AGUUUCCCACAAACCCGGAAGCGGAUCGCGUGGAGUGAAGGUCACGCCGCGGCGCGAUUGACUUCUAAAGAGUCAUGCUGUGUGAUGAAAAAGCCCAGAAGAGAAGGAAGAGGAAAGCAAAGGAGUCAGGGAUGGCUCUUCCUCAGGGACACUUAACAUUCAGGGACGUGGCCAUAGAAUUCUCUCAGGCGGAGUGGAAAUGCCUGGACCCUGCACAGAGGGCUUUAUACAAGGAUGUGAUGUUGGAGAACUACAGGAACCUGGUCUCCCUGGGAAUCUCUCUUCCUGACCUGAAUAUUAACUCCAUGUUGGAGCAAAGGAGGGAGCCCUGGUCUGGUGAGAGUGAAGUGAAAAUAGCAAAAAAUUCAGAUGGGAGGGAGUGCAUCAAAGGUGUGAACACAGGGAGCAGCUAUGCAUUGGGAAGCAAUGCAGAAGACAAACCAAUUAAAAAACAACUUGGAGUAUCCUUUCACUUACAUCUGUCUGAACUGGAGCUAUUUCCAGAUGAAAGGGUAAUAAAUGGAUGUAAUCAAGUUGAAAACUUUAUCAACCACAGUUCCUCUGUUUCCUGUCUUCAAGAAAUGUCUUCCAGUGUCAAAACCCCCAUUUUUAAUAGGAAUGAUUUUGAUGAUUCUUCAUUUCUCCCACAAGAACAGAAAGUACACCUUAGAGAAAAACCUUAUGAAUGUAAUGAGCAUAGCAAAGUCUUUAGAGUAUCUUCCAGCCUUACUAAACAUCAAGUAAUCCAUACUGUAGAGAAACCUUACAAAUGUAAUUCAUGCGGCAAGGUCUUUAGUCGCAAUUCACACCUUGCAGAACAUUGUAGAAUUCAUACUGGAGAGAAACCUUACAAAUGUAAUGUCUGUGGCAAGGUUUUUAGUUACAAUUCAAACUUUGCACGACAUCAAAGAAUUCAUACCAGAGAGAAGCCGUAUGAAUGUAAUGAAUGUGGUAAAGUCUUCAGUAAUAAUUCUUACCUUGCACGACAUCAAAGAAUUCAUGCUGAAGAGAAACCUUACAAAUGUAAUGAAUGUGGUAAAGGCUUCAGUCAUAAGUCAUCUCUAGCAAAUCAUUGGAGAAUUUAUACUGGAGAGAAGCCUUACAAAUGUGAUGAAUGUGGCAAGGCCUUCUAUAGGAUUGCGCUCCUUGUACGACAUCAGAAAAUUCAUACUGGAGAGAAACCUUACAAAUGUAAUGAAUGUGGAAAGGUCUUUAUUCAAAAUUCGCACCUAGCACAACAUUGGAGAAUUCAUACAGGAGAGAAACCUUACAAAUGUAAUGAAUGUGGAAAAGUAUUUAAUCAACUUUCAAAUCUUGCACGACAUCGAAGAAUUCAUACUGGAGAGAAGCCUUACAAAUGUAAUGAAUGUGGUAAAGCAUUUAGUGAGUAUUCAGGCCUUUCAGCCCAUCUUGUAAUCCACACUGGAGAGAAGCCUUACAAAUGUAGUGAAUGUGGCAAGGCAUUCAGACACAAGUUAUCACUAACCAAUCAUCAGAGAAUCCAUACUGGAGAAAGACCUUACAAAUGUAAUGAAUGUGGCAAGGUCUUCAAUCGAAUUGCACACCUUGCACGACAUCGGAAAAUUCAUACUGGAGAGAAACCUUACAAAUGUAAUGAGUGUGGCAAGGCCUUUAGUCGCAUUUCAUACCUAGCACAACAUUGGACAAUUCAUAUGGGAUAGAAACUACAAAUGCAACAAAUGCGUCAAAGAAUUUAGUGUGCACUCAAGCCUUACUACCCAUCUUUUAUUCCAUACUGCAAAGAAAUUUUGCAAAUGUAAAGAAUAUGACAAGGUCUUCAAACACAAGUUUUUCUAAUAACUCAUUAGAGAAUUUAUACUGGAGAGACUUCACAAUUAUAAUAAAUGUGUGGAAAAGUCUUCAAAAAAAUUUCACACCUUGCAAAAGGAGAUCUAAAAAACACAAUCAGAAAUGACAAAGGGGACAUUACCACCAACCCCACAGAAAUACGAAAAACCCUCAAAGAUUACUAUAAACACCUGUAUGCACACAAACUAGAAAACCUAGAAAAAAUUAAUAAAUUCCUUGAAAGAUAUAACCCCCCAAGAUUGAACCAAGAAGAAAUUGCAUCCCUGAACAGACCAAUAAUGAGUUCCAAAAUUUAAUCACUAAUUAAAAAUCUAUCAAACAAAACUCUGGACCAGACAGAUUUAUAGUUGAAGCCUACGAGAUGUAUAAAGAAAAGCUGUUACCAAUCUUACUGAAACUGUUCAAAAACAUGGAUGCAGAGGGACUCCUCCCUAUCUGAUUCUAUGAGGCCAGCAUCAUUCUAAUACCAAAACCUGACAGGCACAAUGAAAAAAGAAAACUUCAGGCUGGUACUCCUGACGAAUAUAGGUGCCAAAAUCCUCAGCAAAAUACUAGUAAACCAAAUCCAUCUGCACAUCAAAAAGCUAAUCCAACAUUAUCAAGCAGGCUUUAGUGUUGGGCUGCAAGGUUGGUUCAGUAUACACAAAUCAAUAAAUGUGAUUUAUCACAUACACAGAACUAAAAACAAAAACCACAUGACCAUGAUCAUCUCUUUAGAUGCAGAAAGGUUUUUAAUAAAAUUCAACAUCCCUUCAUUUUAAAAACCCUCAACAAAUUACACAUUGAGGGAACAUACUUCAAUAAGAACCAUCUAUGCUGGACUCACAGCCAAAUUAAUACUGAACAAGCAAAAGCUGGAAGCAUUCCCCUUGAGAACUGGAAAAUGACAGGGAUGACCACUCUCACCACUCCGAUUCAACAUAGUACUGGAAGUCCUAAGCUUAGUGAUCAGGCAAGAUAAAGAUAUGAAAGGCAUAUAUAAAUAGGAAGAGGGGAAGUCAGUUUCUCUUGCAGAAGAUAUAAUUCUGUAUUUAGAAAACCUGUUGUCUCUGCCCAAAGGCUCCUAGAUCUGAUAAACAACUUCAAAAAAGUUUCAGGAUACAAAAUCUGUGUACAAAAAUUAGUUGCAUUUCUAUACACCAGUAAUGUCCAAGCUAUGAACCAAAUCAAGAAUGGAAUCCCAUUCACAGUAGCCACAAAAAGUAUAAAAUACCUAGGAAUACAGCCAACCAGGUAAGUGAAAGAUUUCUACAAUGAGAAUUACAAAGCAGUGCACAAAGAAAUCAGAAACAAUAAAAAUUGAAAAAUAUCUCAUGCUCAUGGAUAGGAAGAAUCAGUAUUGUUAAAAUACUGCCCAAAGCAAUUUACAGAGCCAAUGCUAUUUCUAUCAAACUACCAAUGGCAUUUUUCACAGAAUCAGAAGAAAACAUUCUGAAAUUUAUUUGGAACCAGAAAAGCCCAACCUAAAUAGCAAAAGCAAUCCUAAGCAAAAAGAGCAAUGUUUGAGGUAUCACACUACCCAACUUUAAACCAUACUACAAGGCUACAGCAACUAAAACAGCAUGGUACUGGUAUAAAAAAAGACACAUAGAUCAAUGGAAUAGGUAAGAGAACCCAGAAAUAAAGGCAUAUACCUACAACCAUGUGAUCCUCAACAAAACUGACAAGCAAUGAAGUAAGAACUUCAUUCAAUAAGUGGUGCUGGCAUAACUGGCUAGCCAUAUGCAGGAUAUUGAAACUGGACCCCUAUCCUUCACGAUAUACAAAAAUCAACUCAAGAUGGAUUAAAGACUUAAAUAUAAAACCUAAAAGUAUUAAAUUCCUAGAAGAAAACCCAGGAAAUGCCAUUCUGGACAUAAGUGCUGGAAAAGACUUAAUGAUGAACACCCCAAAGCAAUUGCAACAAAAACAAAAAUUGACAAGUGGGACCUAAUUAAACUAAAUAACUUCUGCACAGCAAAAGAAGCUAUUUGCAGACUACAGAAUGGGAGAAAAUGUUUACAAACUGCAUCUGACAAAGAUCUAAUCCAGAAUCUAUAAAGAACUCAAACAAAUCAACAAUGAGAAAAACAACCCCAUUAAAAACUGGGCAAAGGCCAUGAAUAGACCUUUCUCAAAAGAAUACAUACAUGUGGCAAUAAGCAUAUGAAAAAAAUGGUUAAUAUCGCUAAUCAUUAAGGAAAUGCAAUCAAAGCCACAAUGAGAUACCAUCUCAGACCUGUCUGAAUGGGUAUUAUCAGAAUGGGUAUUAUUAAAAAAUCAAAACAUAGAUGCUAGUGAGGCUGCAGAGAAAAGCAAAUACUUAUACACUGCUGGUGGGAAUGUAAAUUAAUUCAGCCAUUGUGGAAAGCACUGCAGCGAUUUCUCAAAGACAUAAAAGAACAUAGCAUUCAACCCAGCAUCCCAUUACUGGGUGUAUACCUAAAGGAAUAUAAUCAUUCCACCAUAAAGACAAACACUUGUAUGUUCAUUGCAGCACUAUUCUCAAUAGCAAAGAUGUGGAAUCAACGUAAAUGCCCAUCAGCAGUAGACCAGAUAAAGAAAAUUUGGUACAUAUACACCAUGGAAUACUAUGCAGCCAUAAAAAAGAACAAGACUGUGUCCUUUACAGCAACAUAGAUGGAGCUGAGGCUCUUAUCCUAAGUGAAUUAAUGCAGGAACAGAAAAUGAAAUAUCCCAUGUUCUCACUUAUAAGUGGGAGCUAAACAUUGAUUACACAUGGACUCAAAGAAGGGAACAGUAGACACGGGCUUAUGGGUGGAGGUUGGGAAGAGGAUGAAGAUUGAAUAACUGCCUGUUGGGUACUAUGCUGAUUACCUGGGGACAAAAUUAACUGUACACCAAACUCCUGCAACAUGCAGUUGACCCAUGUACACAUACUCCUUGAACCUAAAAUAAAACAUGAAAAAAAGCAAA